AUUUUGUUCGCCGUUACUCUGCGCGUAAGUCGCUUGUCCGUGGCUUCUCUGAGAAGAAAAGUUGAAAAAGGGUAAAAGUUUUCAGGAAUAUUCGGGCUCUCUAUUGCUAAGCAUAGCGAGUGUCGGUUUUCUCUCUCCAACAGACAUCGCUAUUGCGGUUCCGAGGCAGUGGGAAGAGAUGCGGCCCCUGGACAUCGUCGAGCUGGCGGAACCGGAGGAAGUGGAGGUGCUGGAGCCCGAGGAGGAUUUCGAGCAGUUUCUGCUCCCGGUCAUCAACGAGAUGCGCGAGGACAUCGCGUCGCUGACGCGCGAGCACGGGCGGGCGUACCUGCGGAACCGGAGCAAGCUGUGGGAGAUGGACAAUAUGCUCAUCCAGAUCAAAACGCAGGUGGAGGCCUCGGAGGAGAGCGCCCUCAACCACCUCCAGAACCCGGGCGACGCGGCCGAGGGCCGGGCGGCCAAGAGGUGCGAGAAGGCCGAGGAGAAGGCCAAGGAGAUUGCGAAGAUGGCAGAGAUGCUGGUGGAGCUGGUCCGGCGGAUAGAGAAGAGCGAGUCGUCGUGAGCGCGGUCGGCGGUUUCCAGCCAAUGGAUUCUGGUCAACUGGUGGAGAUUGGCUGACACCCUGGAGAAGCCGAAACCAGAGAGCCUUUUGUUUUCUCUUUUUUCCUGUCUAUGCUCUGUCUCACUUAACACUACGUUUUCUGCUAUGGUCUGUGGUUGAUGACCUCAAUAUGAGUUUCGAUUGUUAACGUGUUUUUGUUUGGGAAGUAAUUUUGUUUGAAAAUGCUCUCACAUACAGGAAUUAGGGCCUAGAUUGUAAGCUCUUGCAGCAGUCACAUUUGUUCCCGGGCUUUGGUGGUUAUUUCUAAAUUUUUGAGGUGCUUUGCUAUUUCUUGUGUGACCUGAUAGCUCCCUGGAACUUUGGGUCUGUGUGUGACACAUGAGACUCACAGUUGGAGUUCUCCAGCUCUGGAGGUGCUGAAGGAGCUGCAUUAAUUCUGGAAGACGACUCCAUGCAGCAACUACUGAAGAAAGGACCAGACUUCAACGGGGAGUGUGGAUGGGCCGACCUGGCUGGGACUCGUGAAUCUGGAGAAGAGCUGGAGAAUGGAUAGUAUUGUCUGUAUUUGGAGACUUUAAUUUCUGUGUGAGACCAAAGGAGGAGAGAUGUGUUUUGUUCAAAAUUUAAAUUUGUUGUGGUACACUAUCUUAUGUAACCUGUCUGGUGAGUUUGUUUGGACAACCUAACUCAGCUUUAUUUGACAUGGAACCUAAAAUAGAAGAUAAGAUCUUGAUAUUCUGUACAAGUUGAUGUAAUACCCUGAUGCGUUUUAGAGGACUUGGCAUAAAAUGAAAGAUUGGCAAAGGCCCUUGAGGGGCUUGGGGAUGACAGUAUGGAACUGUCUGCAUUGGACCCUAAACUGGACUAGAAGAGGCAUCUUCAAGGUUCAUACGUUGUCCAGCUGUAAGUUCAUUUGAGUAGCAGACCUAACAAAUAUUUGAGGUCAGAACCCUACCAUGUUAAAACAAACAAAAACUUACCAUGUUAAUAAAAGUAUUCAUUUGCUUGAAAA